ACUAGCGGCGCCCGGGCGCGGAGUGCGCAGGGCAAGGUCCUGCGCUCUGGGCCAGCGCUCGGCCAUGCGAUCCGCCGCGCGGAGGGGACGCGCCGCGCCCGCCGCCAGGGACUCUUUGCCGGUGCUACUGUUUUUAUGCUUGCUUCUGAAGACGUGUGAACCUAAAACUGCAAAUGCCUUUAAACCAAAUAUCCUACUGAUCAUGGCGGAUGAUCUAGGCACUGGGGAUCUCGGUUGCUACGGGAACAAUACACUGAGAACGCCGAAUAUUGACCAGCUUGCAGAGGAAGGUGUGAGGCUCACUCAGCACCUGGCGGCCGCCCCGCUCUGCACCCCAAGCCGAGCUGCAUUCCUCACAGGGAGACAUUCCUUCAGAUCAGGCAUGGACGCCAGCAAUGGAUACCGGGCCCUUCAGUGGAACGCAGGCUCAGGUGGACUCCCUGAGAACGAAACCACUUUUGCAAGAAUCUUGCAGCAGCAUGGCUAUGCAACCGGCCUCAUAGGAAAAUGGCACCAGGGUGUGAAUUGUGCAUCCCGCGGGGAUCACUGCCACCACCCCCUGAACCACGGAUUUGACUAUUUCUACGGCAUGCCCUUCACGCUCACAAACGACUGUGACCCAGGCAGGCCCCCCGAAGUGGACGCCGCCCUGAGGGCGCAGCUCUGGGGUUACACCCAGUUCCUGGCGCUGGGGAUUCUCACCCUGGCUGCCGGCCAGACCUGCGGUUUCUUCUCUGUCUCCGCGAGAGCAGUCACCGGCAUGGCCGGCGUGGGCUGCCUGUUUUUCAUCUCUUGGUACUCCUCCUUCGGGUUUGUGCGACGCUGGAACUGUAUCCUGAUGAGAAACCAUGACGUCACGGAGCAACCCAUGGUUCUGGAGAAAACAGCGAGUCUUAUGCUAAAGGAAGCUGUUUCCUAUAUUGAAAGACACAAGCAUGGGCCAUUUCUCCUCUUCCUUUCUUUGCUGCAUGUGCACAUUCCCCUUGUGACCACGAGUGCAUUCCUGGGGAAAAGUCAGCAUGGCUUAUAUGGUGAUAAUGUGGAGGAGAUGGACUGGCUCAUAGGUAAGGUUCUUAAUGCCAUCGAAGACAAUGGUUUAAAGAACUCAACAUUCACGUAUUUCACCUCUGACCAUGGAGGACAUUUAGAGGCAAGAGAUGGACACAGCCAGUUAGGGGGAUGGAACGGAAUUUACAAAGGUGGGAAGGGCAUGGGAGGAUGGGAAGGUGGGAUCCGCGUGCCCGGGAUCUUCCACUGGCCGGGGGUGCUCCCGGCCGGCCGAGUGAUUGGAGAGCCCACGAGCCUGAUGGACGUGUUCCCUACUGUGGUCCAGCUGGUGGGUGGCGAGGUGCCCCAGGACAGGGUGAUUGAUGGCCACAGCCUGGUACCCUUGCUGCAGGGAGCUGAGGCACGCUCGGCACAUGAGUUCCUGUUUCAUUACUGUGGGCAGCAUCUUCACGCAGCACGCUGGCACCAGAAGGACAAAAGGUAGUAGAUCGACGCUGAACAGUUUCAACACAGGGGAAAGGGGAAGAAUUAAGGAACCUCUAUGAUUCUGAUUUCUGAAAGCAGCCACAGUGAGCGCUCUGCAAUGAGUCCCUUUGCCUGGGGCAUGCAAUGCAGAGACACAAACGGACACACAUGGGCGCACGCGCGCACACACACAUGCUCUGACUUUGCAAGCUGAAGGCUGUGAUUGUGUGGACUGCCUCGUGUCCCUCCUCCUUUUCACUGAAUAGGGAGGUUCAUGCUGAUACCACAGGGCCGACACCUGCGUUCUGCGUUCACACCUGCGUGGAUUUCUGCCACCCUGACUCCCUUCUUGUCUGCAUCCAGGUGGAAGCGUCUGGAAGGUUCAUUACACGACCCCGCAGUUCCACCCCGAGGGAGCGGGGGCCUGCUACGGCCGAGGCGUCUGCCCAUGCUCCGGGGAGGGCGUGACCCAUCACAGACCCCCUUUGCUCUUUGACCUCUCCAGGGACCCCUCCGAGGCACGGCCCCUGACCCCCGACUCCGAGCCCCUGUACCACGCCGUGAUAGCAAGGGUAGGUGCCGCGGUGUCGGAGCAUCGGCAGACCCUGAGUCCUGUGCCCCAGCAGUUUUCCAUGAGCAACAUCCUGUGGAAGCCGUGGCUGCAGCCGUGCUGCGGACAUUUCCCGUUCUGUUCAUGCCACGAGGAUGGGGAUGGCACCCCCUGAAUGCCAGGACUGUGAGAGAGGAUCCAGGAGAGCCUGACUGCGUUGCAAACAAAAUUCUCCAAGCUUGGUUCUAUCUUCAGCUUCCCUUUUUGCAAGGAACAUGCCCUGGACUGAGAGUGGGUCCCCACUUUCUUUCUUUCUUUCUUUCUUUUUUGAGACAGAGUGUCGCUCUGUCCCUCAGGCUGGAAUGCAAUGGCACGAUCUCUGCUCACUGCAACCUCCGCCUCCCGGGUUCAAGCGAUUUUCCUGCCUCAGCCUCCUGAGUACCCAGGAUUACAGGCACCAGGCACCUGCCACCAUGCCUAGCUAAUUUUUGUAGUUUUAGUAGAGACAGGGUUUCACCAUGUUGCCCAGGCUGGUCUCGCACUCCUGACCUCAAGUCAUCCACCUGCCUCAGCCUCCCAAAGUGCUGGGAUUACAGGCACGAGCCACUGCGCCCAUGUAGGGUUUCCCUUUCCUGAUUUGUGAAAUAAGACUGUCCCAGUAGGCACCCACUGAUGCCUCCUCUUCCUCUUCUAAAUCUCAGGGUUCGUCAUUGUGCCAAUGCCCGAUGUUUUCACCCCUCCGUCUUAAAGCAUUGUUGCAAUUUCAUCACCUAGAUGACAUAACAGCCUUACAAAAGGACAGGGAGGAGUGUCUGUUCCUACUCUCACAUAGCGGAGGAAAGUUAGAGCCUCUCAGUCUCUGUUUAUGAGGACUCAUUAAUCUCAAAUAAUUGAUGCAUUUUUCAUACAUUAGGGUCUCUGUCCAUGUGUCUUCCUGAUAUUGUUAUAGAAAUGGCUUCAGGCUGCUGGUAACAGAUGCUGCGGAAAAAGAAUGCCUUAAACAAAGCCAGGCACGGUGACUCACACCUGUAAUCCCAGCACUUUGGGAGGCUAAGGUGGGAGGAUCACUUGAGCCUAGGAGUUAGACACCUACCCAGCCUGAGCAACACAGUGAGACCUCAUCUCUACAAAAAACAAAUAAUUAGCUAGAUGUCGUGGCGCACAGCUGUAGUCUCAGCUACUUAGGAGGCUGAGGCGGGAGGAUUAUUUGAGCCUGGGAGGUCAAAACUGCAAUGAGCUAAGAUUGCACUACUGCACUCCGGGCUGGGAGACAGAGUAAGACCCUGCCUUAAAAAAAAAAAAAAAAAAAUGCCUUAAAGAAAAUAAUAAGAGAAGGGUGUGUUCUCUUCCAAGUAAUGAGCCGAUCAAGGGGAAGCAACCCAAGGCUAGCAGGCUCUUUUCAAUUCCCAGCUCUGCCACUCUUAGCAUGGCAGAGAGUUGGCCUCAUUAUGCCAGUAUGGCUGCCACAGUGUCAGACAUCACAUUCCAGGCAGUGGAAAGGAGAAAGAACCAAAGGGCAUCCCUUUCUCUUGAAGCAGUCCCUGUGAGGGGGGAUUAUCUGGAAGCCCCAACCCAAUUUCUGCUUCCAACCAUUAUCCAUAGAAACAACUGGAAGUUGAGAAGUGCAGUCUUUUAGGUGGGCACCUGGCUGCCCUGUAUGAAACCAGAAUUAGGUUGGUCAGCAGGAAAACAAGAAAACACUUACUGUGUUGACUGAGGUUUUUGACGCAUCGCUUUAUUGUCAAAUUAAACAACUCUAUCUCAUUCUGCACUGAAACACGUACUACCAUUGCCUAUAAUUGGAAAAUGAUCCUCAGAGGCACAGAAGAUGCCCUGAUGGAAAGUUUGCCCCUUGGGCAAAGAGACAGCCAUGGGAACCUUCAGACAUAGAGAGAGAAGGUGGCUUUUCUCCCUACAUUCCUCAAAUAGCUAAGAUUUGGCCAGUGUGUUUUCUAAGUCAAUUCUAGUGUGUUUCAUCCUCACCUCUUCCCUCUGUGGCUUUGAUGAUGGAAGUGUAGUCCUAACCUACUGCACAGCUGGGACCCCCUGCCCCUAGAUCCCAAUACUGGGGAUGGGAGGACCUUGCACUAUUCCCCUCAGUCCAUCUAUCGAGGUCUUUGCAGGAAGCAUACUGGGAAUUGAAACGAGAGCCUAAAUGACAUCUAAGAAAGGCAGUGUUCAAUACCAGGUAUUAGGUGAGGAUGGGAUUCUAAGGACAUCAGUGGGAGGCAGGGAGCCACCUUCAGACCUCAGCAUGGAAGCUUCCAAGAUCCAGAGGAAGAGGCAACAGCACUGAGAGUCAUAGGUAGAAGAAUCAUCACAGCCCUGCUAACCAGGCAGCUGAUGCCCCUCUCCCCUGGCUCCCUGUGUCCAAAUCCUACAGGGGCAUCUGUUGGCUGAACUCAACCUGAAGCCAAAGAGAAGAUGAGUGGAGAGAGGCAACAUUUAUAGAGCUCAGGUUUCUAGGGCUGGAGAGGGAUCUGGAGGGACACACAGGAGACACCUGGCAUAACCAAAAAAUGAUUAAAAAAAAAAAAAAAAAGAAACAUCUAUGGAGCAUGGGACACGGGGAGUGGAGGCAGCUAAAAGCCAUCUCAUCUUUCACCGUAUUCAACAAGCCCAUUAUAACAAGUCUUUCACGCUCAACCAUUCAAACAAUCCCAACAAUCCCAGCCUAAGAAUUUCCUGGCAUUUGAUGAAAAUGGCUGUGGGUUUUGCUAUCUUUAAGCUCCCUGGGAAGCAGGAUAUAAGCCCAGGGCUGGCAGGCUCUUUCUAGCUACCUGCUCUUGCACAUAGAGUUUGCCUCAUGGUUGCAAGAAGGCUGCCAUAGCUCCAGAUGGCACAUAGACAUUCCAGGCAGCAGGAAAAAGGAAGGAGCACUUAACCGAAGGAGGUCAGGGAGUUGGUUAGUCUCCACCUGAAGAAGAGAGCCAUGAACCAGCUUCAGUUGACUAACGGGCUCCUGUGAGUGCAUCUUUGGACUUUUCUGGAGGUUGAAAUCUAGAUGUGGUAUGUGUCUUAAAGCAGCCACCAACUCCUCCCAUUACCUUCCAAGUGAGCCCAACUACACGAUGGAGCCUCUUCCCUGCCCUUGGAUCUGGGCUGAGCCUCUGACUUGCGUUGACCAACAGAAUGCAGUGAAAGUGAUGCCGAUACUACCCUCCCUGCCCUAGACUUGGGAUACCUGGCAGCUAUAUUCUUCCAUUCCUCAGGACUUGCAAAAACGGGUCUCAGCAUGCCUUCCCAGAGCCAUGAGGUGUUUCUUUGCCCAUUCAUUGAUCUGAGAAGUGAGUGUAAGGAGUUUAAAUCAACCUCUGUUCUGUGCUAGUUAAGGUAAUAAAGUUGCUGCAGUCCAGGGGGUAGGUACCUGUGGACGGCUCUGCGAAUAGGACAGUUGCAUUUCUUGGGAAUCAAGUGCAUCCCUAGGCUGGCAGUGCAGCAGAAAUACUGAAUAAAAUGUGACAAAUCUCCCUG